AACGGCAGCAGCGCGAGCCCAAAUGGGAGGGUGUGCACUACUCUCCAGGAGUGUCUUAAGCUCCUUCCUCCUUCCCCCACCCCCUCCUUGUUUGUAUCUGUGGUUUCGGCGCAUGCGCUGCAGAAGGAGUUAAAUCCCACUACAACCUACGGCGUUGCUGGCCUGAGGGGGGCGAGUUGGGCUGGGUCGGAGUUAGGGGUAUAGUUGCGCGAAGGGGUGGAUGGGGUUGGUAUCGGUAUCUGCACGAAUAGGACUGGGGUAGGGUAAAAUGUCUGCUCGAUUAGAUGAGGAGGUGAGAUGAAGAGAGACCUUUAUUUGAAGGGACUUGAUGAGAGAGAGGUCUCUAAUUUAGUGGCAUCUAGUGGCAAUUUGGGUGGUUAAGAGUUUGGUGAAUAUUGGUGAGAGAGGCGAGGCAGGUUGAUAUAUAUUGGGGAUUUUGAAUCGGUUUGAGUAGAUUAAGGUGGGAUUGUCAUGAGGUAGGUGUAGCUCGAUUCAAGUGUAUAGGUUUGGUUUAAAGAAGGGAAGAUGAGGAUGUCUUGGUUUUAAUUAGAGUUCAACAGGAUACGUGGCAGGUAGUGCAGAUUAGGUCUGGGUUGGCUCCAGGGUUGAGUUGGCAGACCGUUGCUUAUACAGAAGCUGAUAGUUUUGUGUGUGUGUGUUUGUGUGUGUGUGUUUGUGUGGAUAGACUAGGUUAGACCACAGUUUACAGGGUCUGUGGUCAUUUUCUUCUGUAGCUUCCUCUUUGAAAAUUUUAUAAAUUUGAUAAAUCUAGGUGCCACAGUACUGGAAAUUAUACAAAUUGACCCUGGUACUGGGUAACCCUUUGACCAAGUAAUUCCGUCAGGCAAAAACCAGGAGCCCCAUGGCUGGUUUGAGUAUUUUAAGUAAUUUUACAUGCAUGAUCAGAUUUAGAAGGGGCACUUGGCGAAAGUGCAGAAGAUAAUAGGGAUUUUAGUACUGGUUCUAUUACUGAUAUUAUGACAUAGCCAGGUCACUGAUUCUGUGUGCCUGCAUUUUAUAUCUGUACAUUUAGUAACAGUAACCAUGGCUACCUUUAUGGGUCUUCUGAAGAUGAAUGAGAACAGUGUUAGUAAAGGGUUUUCAGGUCCCUGGAAAAGGAAUACAGUUUAAUUGCUCUAAUGCUAGAAAAUUUACAGAAACACUCAACACCCCAUGCUGCAUUCCAGCCAAAUUCCCAGAUUGGUGAGGAAAUGAGCCAGAACAGUUUCAUAAAACAGUAUCUGGAAAAGCAGCAGGAGCUACUUAGGCAGCGUCUGGAACGUGAAGCUCGAGAAGCUGCAGAACUUGAAGAAGCUUCAGCUGAGUCGGAGGACGAGAUGAUCCAUCCUGAGGGAGUGGCUUCCCUGCUGCCUCCUGACUUUCAGAGCAGCCUGGAGAGACCAGAGCUGGAGCUCAGCAGACAUUCGCCCAGAAAAAGCUCCUCAAUUUCUGAAGAGAAAGGUGACUCUGAUGAUGAGAAACCAAGGAAAGGAGAAAGACGAUCAUCUAGGGUCAGACAGGCAAGAGCAGCUAAACUGUCUGAGGGCAGCCAACCUGCUGAGGAGGAAGAGGAUCAAGAAACACCUUCCAGAAACCUAAGGGUCAGAGCAGAUCGAAAUUUGAAAACAGAGGAGGAAGAAGAGGAGGAGGAGGAGGAGGAAGAAGAUGAUGAAGAAGAGGAAGGUGAUGAUGAGGGACAAAAAUCUAGGGAGGCACCAAUCCUGAAAGAGUUUAAGGAAGAAGGGGAAGAGAUACCUAGAGUAAAACCAGAGGAGAUGAUGGAUGAGAGACCCAAAACAAGAUCCCAGGAACAGGAGGUGUUAGAGAGAGGAGGGAGAUUUACAAGAUCCCAGGAAGAGGCUAGAAAAAGUCAUCUGGCCAGACAGCAGCAGGAGAAGGAAAUGAAAACAACAUCUCCCCUUGAGGAGGAAGAAAGAGAAAUAAAAUCUUCACAAGGCUUAAAGGAAAAAUCGAAGUCUCCUUCCCCUCCUCGACUGACUGAAGAUCGAAAGAAGGCCUCACUUGUAGCGCUGCCAGAGCAAACUGCCAGCGAGGAGGAGACUCCUCCACCUUUACUAACAAAGGAAGCAUCUUCUCCACCACCUCAUCCACAGCUCCAUAGCGAAGAAGAAAUAGAGCCCAUGGAAGGCCCAGCCCCCGCUGUCCUCAUUCAGUUAUCUCCUCCUAAUACAGAUGCUGACACCAGGGAGCUAUUAGUAUCUCAGCAUACUGUCCAGUUGGUAGGAGGCCUGUCUCCUUUGUCAAGUCCUUCAGACACCAAAGCAGAAUCUCCAGCAGAGAAAGUGCCAGAGGAGAGUGUCCUGCCUCUGGUUCAGAAAAGCACACUGGCUGACUACUCAGCCCAGAAGGAUCUUGAACCUGAGUCAGACAGAUCUGCUCAGCCCCUCCCUCUAAAAAUUGAGGAAUUAGCACUGGCCAAAGGAAUCACUGAAGAAUGUCUGAAACAGCCAUCUUUGGAACAGAAGGAAGGCAGAAGAGCUUCUCAUACCCUUCUCCCAAGCCACAGAUUGAAACAGUCAGCUGAUUCAUCCUCUAGCCGGUCCUCCUCAUCUUCCUCCUCCAGUUCUAGAUCAAGAUCUCGCUCUCCUGACAGUUCAGGUUCUCGGUCUCAUUCACCGCUCAGAUCCAAGCAGAGAGAUGUAGCCCAGGCACGUACUCAUGCCAACCCUCGUGGUAGACCCAAGAUGGGCUCCAGAUCAACAUCAGAGUCCAGAUCAAGGUCACGUUCACGUUCUCGUUCAGCAUCAAGCAACAGCAGAAAAUCUCUGAGCCCUGGAGUCUCCAGGGACAGCAGCACCAGCUAUACUGAAACCAAAGAUCCCUCUUCUGGUCAGGAGGUUGCAACUCCACCAGUGCCACAACUGCAGGUCUGUGAGCCAAAGGAGAGGACUUCCACCUCCUCAUCCUCUGUCCAAGCAAGGCGUCUGAGUCAGCCUGAAUCAGCUGAAAAGCAUGUGACCCAGAGGUUACAGCCUGAGCGGGGGAGCCCAAAGAAGUGUGAAGCUGAAGAGGCAGAGCCACCAGCUGCCACACAGCCCCAAACCUCAGAGACUCAGACCUCUCAUCUGCCAGAAUCAGAAAGAAUUCAUCACACUGUUGAGGAGAAGGAGGAAGUGACCAUGGACACAAGUGAAAACAGACCUGAAAAUGAUGUUCCAGAACCUCCCAUGCCUAUUGCAGACCAAGUCAGCAAUGAUGACCGCCCGGAGGGCAGUGUUGAAGAUGAGGAGAAGAAAGAGAGCUCGCUGCCCAAAUCAUUCAAGAGGAAGAUCUCCGUUGUCUCAGCUACCAAGGGGGUGCCAGCUGGAAACAGUGACACAGAGGGGGGCCAGCCUGGUCGGAAACGACGCUGGGGAGCCAGCACAGCCACCACACAGAAGAAACCUUCCAUCAGUAUCACCACUGAAUCACUAAAGAGCCUCAUCCCCGACAUCAAACCCCUGGCGGGGCAGGAGGCUGUUGUGGAUCUUCAUGCUGAUGACUCUCGCAUCUCUGAGGAUGAGACAGAGCGUAAUGGCGAUGAUGGGACCCAUGACAAGGGGCUGAAAAUAUGCCGGACAGUCACUCAGGUAGUACCUGCAGAGGGCCAGGAGAAUGGGCAGAGGGAAGAAGAGGAAGAAGAGAAGGAACCUGAAGCAGAACCUCCUGUACCUCCCCAGGUGUCAGUAGAGGUGGCCUUGCCCCCACCUGCAGAGCAUGAAGUAAAGAAAGUGACUUUAGGAGAUACCUUAACUCGACGUUCCAUUAGCCAGCAGAAGUCCGGAGUUUCCAUUACCAUUGAUGACCCAGUCCGAACUGCCCAGGUGCCCUCCCCACCCCGGGGCAAGAUUAGCAACAUUGUCCAUAUCUCCAAUUUGGUCCGUCCUUUCACUUUAGGCCAGCUAAAGGAGUUGUUGGGGCGCACAGGAACCUUGGUGGAAGAGGCCUUCUGGAUUGACAAGAUCAAAUCUCAUUGCUUUGUAACGUACUCAACAGUAGAGGAAGCUGUUGCCACCCGCACAGCUCUGCACGGGGUCAAAUGGCCCCAGUCCAAUCCCAAAUUCCUUUGUGCUGACUAUGCCGAGCAAGAUGAGCUGGAUUAUCACCGAGGCCUCUUGGUGGACCGUCCCUCUGAAACUAAGACAGAGGAGCAGGGAAUACCACGGCCCCUGCACCCCCCACCCCCACCCCCGGUCCAGCCACCACAGCACCCCCGGGCAGAGCAGCGGGAGCAGGAACGGGCAGUGCGGGAACAGUGGGCAGAACGGGAACGGGAAAUGGAGCGGCGGGAGCGGACUCGAUCAGAGCGUGAAUGGGAUCGGGACAAAGUUCGAGAAGGGCCCCGUUCCCGAUCAAGGUCCCGUGACCGCCGCCGCAAGGAACGUGCGAAGUCUAAAGAAAAGAAGAGUGAGAAGAAAGAGAAAGCCCAGGAGGAACCACCUGCCAAGCUGCUGGAUGACCUUUUCCGAAAGACCAAGGCAGCUCCCUGCAUCUAUUGGCUCCCACUGACUGACAGCCAGAUCGUUCAGAAAGAGGCAGAGCGGGCCGAACGGGCCAAGGAGCGGGAGAAGCGGCGAAAGGAGCAAGAAGAAGAAGAGCAAAAGGAGCGGGAGAAGGAAGCCGAGCGGGAACGGAACCGACAGCUGGAGCGAGAGAAACGUCGGGAGCACAGUCGGGAGAGGGACAGGGAGAGAGAGAGAGAAAGGGAGCGGGACAGGGGGGACCGAGAUCGGGAUAGGGAAAGGGACCGAGAACGAGGCAGGGAAAGGGAUCGCAGGGACACCAAGCGCCACAGCAGAAGCCGGAGUCGGAGCACACCUGUGCGGGACCGGGGUGGGCGCCGCUAGCUGGGAAAACACUAGAGCUGCAGGUACCAGCCACUCGGCCCCAGGGGGUUAUGGCCACAGAGGGAUAGGCACAGUCUCCACCACCCUGGAGCCAAGGGUCUUUCACAUCACCUAUCCCUACAUACAUACCAAAUGGAAAAGUGGCCAUCCUUUUCCCCCCAAACACACCCCCUUAACCUAUCUCUUGGGACUUAGCCCGACCCUCCCUCUCAUUUCCCAUUAAGUCUGAGAGGCAAGAGCUAGGUUAGGCAAGGAGGUGGUUGGCCAGAGAUGGGGAACAGCCAGGUGCCCCAGUCCUCUGAUUUUUCCUCCAUCCUGCUUACCACCUCCCUGGGUACUUACAGCCUUCUCUUGGGAACAGCCGGGGCCAGGACUGGGUCACCUAUGAGCUGAAUCAGCAUCUCCUCCUGAGUCCCAGGGCCCCUGCAGUUCCCAGUCUCUUCUGUCCUGCAGCCCUUGCCUCUUUCCCACAGGUUCCACUUUAUAUCCACCUUUUCCUUUUGUUCAAUUUUUAUUUUUAUUUUUUUUAUUAUUAAAUGAUGUGGUCUAUGGAAAAAAAAAUAAAAAUCUGACUUAGUUUUAAA